GAAACACAGACUGGGAGCGGGCGGGAGCGGGAGCGCGGCGCACGCCCCGGGCCGGCCCAGCCAGCGAGCGAGCGAGCGGCGAGCCGGGAGGAGGAGGGUGGCGGGGCGGUGAGGCCGCAGAGGCGGAGGGAUCUGCGCAUCAAAGCUAGCGAGGCGAGCGAAGUUUGGCCGGGGGUUGGACUUUCCUUCCCGGAGGCGGCACCCAAACAGCUACCCCGUGCGGAAACCCAAACUUCUGCUGCCACUUGGAGUCUCGCGGCCGCCGCCUCCGCCCCGCGUUCGGGGCCUUCCCGACCCUGCACUGCUGCCGUCCGCCCGCCCGGCCGCUCUUCUCUUCGCCGUGGGAGCCGCUCCGGGCGCAGGGCCGCGCGCCGAGCCCCGCAGGCUGCAGCGCCGCGGCCCGGCCCGGCGCCCCGGCAACUUCGCCGAGAGUUGAGGCGAAGUUUGGGCGACCGCGGCAGGCCCCGGCCGAGCUCCCCUCUGCGCCCCCGGCGUCCCGUCGAGCCCAGCCCCGCCGGGGGCGCUCCUCGCCGCCCGCGCGCCCUCCCCAGCCAUGUCGUCCAUCCUGCCUUUCACUCCCCCGAUCGUGAAGCGCCUGCUGGGCUGGAAGAAGGGCGAGCAGAACGGGCAGGAGGAGAAAUGGUGCGAGAAGGCGGUCAAGAGCCUGGUCAAGAAACUCAAGAAGACGGGGCAGCUGGACGAGCUGGAGAAGGCCAUCACCACGCAGAACGUCAACACCAAGUGCAUCACCAUCCCCAGGUCCCUGGAUGGCCGGUUGCAGGUGUCCCAUCGGAAGGGGCUCCCUCAUGUCAUCUACUGCCGCCUGUGGCGAUGGCCAGACCUGCACAGCCACCACGAGCUACGGGCCAUGGAGCUGUGUGAGUUCGCCUUCAAUAUGAAGAAGGACGAGGUCUGCGUGAAUCCCUACCACUACCAGAGAGUAGAGACACCAGUUCUACCUCCUGUGUUGGUGCCACGCCACACAGAGAUCCCGGCCGAGUUCCCCCCACUGGACGACUACAGCCAUUCCAUCCCCGAAAACACUAACUUCCCCGCAGGCAUCGAGCCCCAGAGCAAUAUUCCAGAGACCCCACCCCCUGGCUACCUGAGUGAAGAUGGAGAAACCAGUGACCACCAGAUGAACCACAGCAUGGACGCAGGUUCUCCAAACCUAUCCCCGAAUCCGAUGUCCCCAGCACAUAAUAACUUGGACCUGCAGCCAGUUACCUACUGCGAGCCGGCCUUCUGGUGCUCCAUCUCCUACUACGAGCUGAACCAGCGCGUCGGGGAGACAUUCCACGCCUCGCAGCCAUCCAUGACUGUGGAUGGCUUCACCGACCCCUCCAAUUCGGAGCGCUUCUGCCUAGGGCUGCUCUCCAAUGUCAACAGGAAUGCAGCAGUGGAGCUGACACGGAGACACAUCGGAAGAGGCGUGCGGCUCUACUACAUCGGAGGGGAGGUCUUCGCAGAGUGCCUCAGUGACAGCGCUAUUUUUGUCCAGUCUCCCAACUGUAACCAGCGCUAUGGCUGGCACCCGGCCACCGUCUGCAAGAUCCCACCAGGAAAGGCCCCCCUCUCCACACCAUCUCCCUAUUUUUGGAAGCCCUCUUUGCAGACUUCUCCCUGCUCUGGGAGUCGGAGCUUGUGGGCCAGCCUUCCAUCUCCCCUUGCAGGAUGCAACCUGAAGAUCUUCAACAACCAGGAGUUCGCUGCCCUCCUGGCCCAGUCGGUCAACCAGGGCUUUGAGGCUGUCUACCAGUUGACCCGAAUGUGCACCAUCCGCAUGAGCUUCGUCAAAGGCUGGGGAGCGGAGUACAGGAGACAGACUGUGACCAGUACCCCCUGCUGGAUUGAGCUGCACCUGAAUGGGCCUUUGCAGUGGCUUGACAAGGUCCUCACCCAGAUGGGCUCCCCAAGCAUCCGCUGUUCCAGUGUGUCUUAGAGACAUCAAGUAUGGUAGGGGAGGGCAGGCUUGGGGAAAAUGGCCAUGCAGGAGGUGGAGAAAAUUGGAACUCUACUCAACCCAUUGUUGUCAAGGAAGAAGAAAUCUUUCUCCCUCAACUGAAGGGGUGCACCCACCUGUUUUCUGAAACACACGAGCAAACCCAGAGGUGGAUGUUAUGAACAGCUGUGUCUGCCAAACACAUUUACCCUUUGGCCCCACUUUGAAGGGCAAGAAAUGGCGUCUGCUCUGGUGGCUUAAGUGAGCAGAACAGGUAGUAUUACACCACCGGCCCCCUCCCCCCAGACUCUUUUUUUGAGUGACAGCUUUCUGGGAUGUCACAGUCCAACCAGAAACACCCCUCUGUCUAGGACUGCAGUGUGGAGUUCACCUUGGAAGGGCGUUCUAGGUAGGAAGAGCCCGCAGGGCCAUGCAGACCUCAUGCCCAGCUCUCUGACGCUUGUGACAGUGCCUCUUCCAGUGAACAUUCCCAGCCCAGCCCCGCCCCGCCCCGCCCCACCACUCCAGCAGACCUUGCCCCUUGUGAGCUGGAUAGACUUGGGAUGGGGAGGGAGGGAGUUUUGUCUGUCUCCCUCCCCUCUCAGAACAUACUGAUUGGGAGGUGCGUGUUCAGCAGAACCUGCACACAGGACAGCGGGAAAAAUCGAUGAGCGCCACCUCUUUAAAAACUCACUUACGUUUGUCCUUUUUCACUUUGAAAAGUUGGAAGGAUCUGCUGAGGCCCAGUGCAUAUGCAAUGUAUAGUGUCUAUUAUCACAUUAAUCUCAAAGAGAUUCGAAUGACGGUAAGUGUUCUCAUGAAGCAGGAGGCCCUUGUCGUGGGAUGGCAUUUGGUCUCAGGCAGCACCACACUGGGUGCGUCUCCAGUCAUCUGUAAGAGCUUGCUCCAGAUUCUGAUGCAUACGGCUAUAUUGGUUUAUGUAGUCAGUUGCAUUCAUUAAAUCAACUUUAUCAUAUGCUCUUUUAAAUGUUUGGUUUAUAUAUUUUCUUUAAAAAUCCUGGGCUGGCACAUUGACUGGGAAACCUGAGUGAGACCCAGCAACUGCUUCUCUCCCUUCUCUCUCCUGAGGUGAAGCUUUUCCAGGUUUUGUUGAAGAGAUACCUGCCAGCACUUCUGCAAGCUGAAAUUUACAGAAGCAAAUUCACCAGAAGGGAAACAUCUCAGGCCAACAUAGGCAAAUGAAAAGGGCUAUUAAAAUAUUUUUACACCUUUGAAAAUUGCAGGCUUGGUACAAAGAGGUCUGUCAUCUUCCCCCUGGGAUAUAAGAUGAUCUAGCUCCCGGUAGAGGAUCACCGGUGACAACUAUAGCAGUUGUAUUGUGUAACAAGUACUGCUCCCAGCAGCAAUUAGGGAGAAAACUAGUCUAAAUUAUUUCAACUGGAAAAAAGAAAAAAGAGUCCUCUUCUUUUCCCAGCCUUUUGCAGAACACAGUAGACAGAACUGCCACCUUCAAUUGGUACUUUAUUCUUUGCUGCUGUUUUUGUAUAAAAUGACCUAUCCCACGUUUUUGCAUGAAUUUAUAGCAGGAAAAAUCAAGGGAUUUCCUAUGGAAGUCCUGCUUUAUUCCAGGUGAAGGGAAGGAAGUGUAUAUACUUUUGGCAAGUCAUACAGCUCAAAUGUGAUGAGAUUUCUGAUGUUAGAGGGAGAUGGAGAGGCUUCCUGAUGCCUCAUCUGCAGGGUCCUGUGCCUCUGAAGUUCUAGCCAUGAGGUUUCCAGGUAGGACAGCUGCUCCCCAAGCCUCCUGAGGACACAGGAAGAGACGGAAGGAGCACCUUGACAGACUUGUGUGAGUCUUCUCGAAGGAGGGUUGACUCAGAACCCAGAGACAAUACAAAACCCCUCACUUCCUCUGAGAGGGCCAAAUGCUGUGAGUCUGAAGUAUGUGCCUGGUGUGAAAUGAUCUAUGGCCUGUUUCUUACACAGGAAGCCCCCUGAACCUCCUGUACAUGUGUUCAUGUUCCCAGCCAGCUCUGAGACCCAGGAACCAAAUAUUCCAUUUUGGCUUCUGCUAGAGCAGUCAUGGUUCCUCUCCUAAAAGCCAUGGGCAGCAGUUUCCGAGGGCCUGCAUGAUCCACCUGCUGCACGAUCCUAUGAGGGCUUCCUGUGGCACACAGCCCUCUGGGUGCUUGGGAACUAGCUUCAGGCACAGCCUGAUUCUGGUGAUCCAGUGAUCUAUGGAAGUCGUGUCUUACUCCAGGUGAAGGGGGAAAAAAAAAGCCUAUACUUUGGCAGGUUAUGAACUUUGAAUGUGAUGAAAUGACACGUUUGGCUGCAUUUGGAUGGUGUCUUAGAACCCUCAUUGCUCAGACCUGAAGGCUACUUCUAGGAGCAUGAAGUUUGAGUUUUGUGUUUUUCCAAAGGAUACUUCCUUGGCCCUUUUUCUUUAUUGACUAGACCACCAGAGGAGGAUGUGUGGGAUUGUAGGCAAACCCACCUGUGGCAUCACUGAAAAUAAAUUUGAUCAUACCUAAGAGGUUAGGAAAUGGUGCCAUUCCCACCUUAGAGUGCUACAUAGGUGCUUUGGGCGUAUGUAACAUUAGUGUCCUUCCUUGAAGCCACAAGCUAGUUUUCUUAGUUUUAAAAUCCUGUUGUAUGAAUGGCAUUUGUAUAUUAAAACACUUUUUUAAAGGACAGUUGAAAAGGGCAAGAGGAAACCAGGGCAGUUCUAGAGGAGUGCUGGUGACUGGAUAGCAGUUUUAAGUGGCGUUCACCUAGUCAACACGACCGCGUGUGUUGCCCCUGCCCUGGGCUCCCCGCCAUGACAUCUUCACCUUGCAGCUUGUGCUGAGACUGACCCAAGUGCAGCUAGCACUGGGACACAGAUCCUUGUCUUCAGCACCUUCCAAGGAGCCAACUUUUAUUCCCUUUCCUCUCUCCCCUCCCCACCUCGCUUCUUCCCAAUUUAGUAACUUAGAUGCUUCCAGCACAUACGUAGGUAGCUACCCCAGCCGGUUUGGAUUACAGGCCUGUGCUGGAACAUCAUCUCAGUUGGCCACCUUCCUGGCAGGCUGUAGACCUGACAUUUUGAGACAAGCCUAGAGGAGUCAGGAGCAGGGACUUUGACUCUUAGGAAGAGCACACAUGAGGGCAAGGCUGCUGGCAGACGUCUCCAUUGUCCUUAUGUUGUCUGUGUUGUAUUUUUUUUUUUUUAUUGACCAUGGUGAUUAUUUUUUUAAACCAUCGUUAAUAUACUGAAGUGAGCUAUAGCACAUAUCAUGUGCUUAGUUUGUUUAUUUUUCUCCAUCUCCCCUUGGCUUCCUAGAGUUUGGACAUAUUCCAGGCUAAAUGCUUUUACUCAAGACUACAGAAAGGUUUGAAGUAGUGUGUGCAUGGCAUGCACGUAUGUAAGUAAUCUGGGGAAGAAGCAAAGAUCUGUUUCAUUCUUAGCCUCAGGCCUCAUGAGGGUCUCCACAGGGCCGGAGCUCAGGUUACACCACUCCUUCGUCCUUACAGGAGAUGUAGGGAGAAGAAUCUGCAGGCUGCUUGUAGGACUGUUCACCAAGGGGGAUACCAGCAGCAAGAGAGUGCACCCGUUUAGCCCUGGACCCUGUUUCUUACUGUGUGACUUGGCUAGAGUUGGGAGUUCCCCCAAAAUAAACGUGUCCCCAUUUUACCAGAACCAAACCUCAACACAGCGAAGCUGUACUGUCUUUGUGUGGCAAAGAUGUUCCCUUGUAGGCCCCUUUCAGGUAACCGUCUUCACAAUGUAUUUUCAUCACAGUUUAAGGAGCAUCAGCCGCUUCUCAAGUGGGUAGGGAAAGCAGAAAAACGUACGCAAGAGGACAUGGAUCCAAAAUGAUGAUGAAGCAUCUCCCAUGGGGAGGUGAUGGUGGGGAGAUGAUGGGCUAAACAGGCAACUUUUCAAAAACACAGCUAUCAUAGAAAAGAAACUUGCCUCAUGUAAACUGGAUUGAGAAAUUCUCAGUGAUUCUGCAAUGGAUUUUUUUUUAAUGCAGAAGUAAUGUAUACUCUAGUAUUCUGGUGUUUUUAUAUUUAUGUAAUAAUUUCUUAAAACCAUUCAGACAGAUAACUAUUUAAUUUUUUUUAAGAAAGUUGGAAAGGUCUCUCCUCCCAAGGACAGUGGCUGGAAGAGUUGGGGCACAGCCAGUUCUGAAUGUUGGUGGAGGGUGUAGUGGCUUUUUGGCUCAGCAUCCAGAAACACCAAACCAGGCUGGCUAAACAAGUGGCCGCGUGUAAAAACAGACAGCUCUGAGUCAAAUCUGGGCCCUUCCACAAGGGUCCUCUGAACCAAGCCCCACUCCCUUGCUAGGGGUGAAAGCAUUACAGAGAGAUGGAGCCAUCUAUCCAAGAAGCCUUCACUCACCUUCACUGCUGCUGUUGCAACUCGGCUGUUCUGGACUCUGAUGUGUGUGGAGGGAUGGGGAAUAGAACAUUGACUGUGUUGAUUACCUUCACUAUUCGGCCAGCCUGACCUUUUAAUAACUUUGUAAAAAGCAUGUAUGUAUUUAUAGUGUUUUAGAUUUUUCUAACUUUUAUAUCUUAAAAGCAGAGCACCUGUUUAAGCAUUGUACCCCUAUUGUUAAAGAUUUGUGUCCUCUCAUUCCCUCUCUUCCUCUUGUAAGUGCCCUUCUAAUAAACUUUUCAUGGAAAA